AGCCGCGCCGCCACUUCAGGUCCAGGGUGGACGCAUGCCCUCAGGUGCGGGCGUCUUGCGAGUCGGCCUCGCAGCUCUGUGGAAGCUGCACGCGGCUUGUCGGAAAAUCAAGGCGUUCUGAGUUCUAGAUGGUUAAUAGCAGGUUCUUCGGUGUCUGCAGUCGACGAACGACUGGUGUAGGCGUUUGCUGUGAGAAUGGAGAAUGCAGGGGAACGCCCCUGACUGAGAAGCGGGCCCUGGGAAACGAUUGUGAACGCGUGAAUGAAUUGAUGACUAAAAUCCGCUGCGGGGGUCCUACAGCGCAGAUGGUAAUGCCGUUCUGACUGGCUGGGAACGGCACCUUAGCAGAUACUUAAAAGGCGCCUUCUGUGUGCCACUGUCACUGCCAACUUGGUGACUCAUUUAAAACUCAUAACCAGCCGGUGAGGUCGGUACUUCGCUCCUCCUCAUUCUGCGGAGGGGAAAGCAGCACGGAAAUGCCCUGUGACUGGCAGCGGAAAAGGCGACCACCGCUUGUGUGUGGGUGUCCCGACGUCCGGAGGGGGCAGGAGUUUCCACGGGUCCUGGGACAGAGCUCACCUGUUUUGUUUUGAAUUACACUUAUUUAUAUGCAACUACAGGCCUGACGCUAGCGGUGAAGAAGGCAGAUACAGCCUUUUAAGGAGUUGGCAGAUGAGUGGGAGAGAGAAAACUAAUCUCAUUAUCGGCCACAGGCUGUGGUCAGUGUUUUGAAGGAAAAGUACAGGGAUGUUUGGCAACUGUGGUAUUUCAGGUUUGACCUUAAAUCCUUACUUAAACCAAUUUUUACAAGGAUUGGUCUAGGUGCCCGGGCGCGGUGGCUCACGCCUAUAAUCCCAGCACUUUAGGAGGCCGAGGCGGGCGGAUCACGAAAUCAGGAGAUCGAGACCGUCGUGGCUAACACGUUUACGUUGUUAAAGGGAAGCUGGACGAGAUAAUAAAGGUAGAAACAGCAUAACUGCUGAGCAGUUGGAUGUGGAGUUUGGAAGAAGAUAAUGAGUCAGUGUGGGUGACUGCAAAGUCCUGGGCCUCAACCACUUGAAGGAUGUAUGGAGUGGUCAUUAACUGGGAGAGUGAAAAAUUAUGAGUAGGGCUGGUUUGGGUGAGGGAAAGAGACUUGAAGAUCAUGGAGUGAUCUAGAAGGCAAGGAAAAUGUUUUGUGUAUUCCUGUUUACAUCUCUGCCAGCAUUAUAAUUAGCCCAUAAUUGGCACUAAAAUUAUUGAAUAAAUCAAAGAAUAUAUAAGCUAAUCUUGUACCCUUCCAUAGAUCAAAGCAGUUUAAGGAUAAGUUUUCACAAUUUGAGUCACACACCUUUACCAAAAGUCCUUGAAAACUGUAUACAGGAAUACAUACUAGUUCAAGUAAAAAUUUCUCCAGUUCUACCCUCAAAUAGAGGACUAUUUCAGAUUCUUGAGUAAAGGUGGAUUGUGUAACAACUUUCUCAAGCCAUGGCUCCUCCUUGCUUUUUAUGAUCCCUGGUGUCCACAAUUUGAAGCUCUACCCUGAAGCUCUAUCCUGAAAUACAUUUGCCCUCUGUUCUGCCUUCAUAGUGACACAACUUUAAGUUCAUGGCUCUUUUACUAUCCUUGUGGAAUGGCAUCUUUUUAUUGUCUCUGCUAAAGUUCCCUUCUGCGAAGAGACUUUCCUUUAAUAGGACUACAUUACUGCAUUGUCCCCACUUUGCUCGGCUGGUAGCCAUUCCCUUUUACUUAGAACUCUUCUACUGUCACUUUUGACUAAUACCACUGCUUAUGGCAGGCAGUCCAUGUUCUUUUCCCAAGGUUCUGGAUAUACCUAGUGCUCACUUGGCAGAGCCCACCCGUGUGCCAAAGACUCUGGUGGCCCCAUUACUCAGCUGGUUAGUUGUUACCACUUGGCAGUCCUCAUGACCUUUGCUGAUAUAACUUUCUGCUGAACUUUUGUUCUCUGCUAAGCCUCCUGUUUUCUUCUGAAGUAGUGUGUACCAUGGCUAAAUCUCCUUGACUUGUUUGCACAGGGAUAAGGCUUGUCUCAGUAUUUUGGCUGUAAAAUGCUAUCCUGAAAGGAUGGCAAUAAGCAAUCUUUACAUUCCACUGAUAAGGGAAUAUCGUUCUCUCACUGACUGGCCUCUUAUAUUGGGUUAACUAGAAUAGACUACAGGAGGUGUGACAUUGUAAGUGAACCUGGGGUGAGGCACAGGGCAGACAACUCCAGCAAGGCAUGGAAUGGAUCCUGUUUUGCCUUCCCCUUAACUGAGAGGCAGCCACCUAACCUAUGUGGUAAAUGCCUUUCCUCCAAGGUUAGGUUCCCUUAGAGCCCUCUUCAUUCACUUUGUGGAAUACAGAGAGCCAAAUACAAAUGGGCUUAGUUACAAUAUGUUUAUACUUCAAAGUUGUCUCUCAGGUAUUUGACAAUCCUCUCCCUCACUAGCCUCAUUCAUCUUGGAAAUAGAAGGAGAUUCCUAGAUAUCAUUGAACAUUUUGAGGUAAAAUGAAUCAUAAAAGAGCAUAUAUAUCAAAUAUAUUUUCUAUGGCAAUACUGAAGCCCAGAUAGGUUAAGUGUUCUGCUCAGAGUCUUUUAUCUGUUUAAUGGCAAACCUUAAACUAGACCCAGGCCUCCCGAGUCCAGUACCCUUUUCAUUAUACUGUUGGUAAGACUGUGACUUUAGGCACUGAAUGGCAUAAUGAAAUCACACAGUUUUGCAUGCCUUAUAGAAGGAGGGCACUCUGAACAUUGUCAGUUGAGUAAUAACUGCCUAUAUUUUCAGGGACGUAACAAAUCCUGGAAGAGCCGCACUUACCACUUGUAGAUUUCCAUGGUUAUAUUUCUCCAUACAUGCUGUCAUUUAAAUGUUGUUUUUCUUCUCUUCUCAAAGAUCUUCAGUUUAGAUCUUGGAGGCAUAUCAACUGUGGUUCUAAAUGGCUAUGAUGUAGUAAAGGAAUGCCUUGUUCAUCAAAGCGAAAUUUUUGCAGACAGACCAUGCCUUCCUUUAUUCAUGAAGAUGACAAAAAUGGGAGGCUUACUCAAUUCCAGAUAUGGCCGAGGAUGGGUUGAUCACAGACGAUUAGCUGUAAACAGUUUUCGAUAUUUUGGAUAUGGCCAAAAGUCUUUUGAAUCUAAAAUCUUGGAAGAAACCAAAUUUUUCAAUGAUGCUAUUGAAACAUACAAAGGUAGACCUUUUGACUUUAAACAGUUAAUAACGAAUGCUGUUUCAAACAUAACCAAUCUGAUCAUUUUUGGAGAACGAUUCACUUAUGAAGACACCGAUUUUCAGCACAUGAUUGAGUUAUUUAGUGAAAAUGUGGAACUAGCUGCCAGUGCCUCAGUCUUCUUGUAUAAUGCCUUUCCAUGGAUUGGCAUCCUGCCUUUUGGAAAACAUCAACAGCUGUUUAGAAAUGCAGCUGUAGUCUAUGAUUUUCUCUCCAGACUCAUUGAAAAAGCUUCAGUCAACAGAAAGCCUCAGCUACCUCAGCAUUUUGUUGAUGCUUAUUUAGAUGAGAUGGAUCAAGGUAAAAAUGACCCAUCAUCUACUUUCUCCAAAGAAAACCUAAUUUUCUCAGUGGGUGAACUCAUCAUUGCUGGAACUGAAACUACAACCAAUGUGCUACGGUGGGCGAUUCUUUUCAUGGCCCUUUAUCCUAAUAUUCAAGGACAAGUUCAGAAAGAGAUUGAUUUAAUUAUGGGCCCUAAUGGGAAGCCUUCUUGGGACGACAAAUGCAAAAUGCCUUAUACUGAGGCAGUUUUGCAUGAAGUUUUAAGAUUCUGUAAUAUAGUUCCAUUAGGGAUUUUCCAUGCAACCUCUGAAGAUGCAGUUGUACGUGGUUAUUCCAUUCCUAAAGGCACAACAGUAAUUACAAAUCUUUAUUCUGUACACUUUGAUGAAAAGUACUGGAGAGACCCAGAAGUGUUCCAUCCUGAGCGAUUUCUGGACAGCAGUGGAUAUUUUGCCAAGAAGGAAGCUUUGGUUCCUUUUUCCCUAGGAAGAAGACAUUGUCUUGGAGAACACUUGGCUCGGAUGGAAAUGUUCUUGUUUUUUACAGCAUUGCUUCAGAGGUUUCAUUUGCAUUUUCCACAUGAACUAGUUCCAGAUCUGAAGCCCAGGUUAGGCAUGACAUUGCAGCCCCAACCCUACCUCAUCUGUGCUGAAAGACGCUGAAACUGCCUGGGAUGUUUUCGGGAACAAGAAUGUAUAUUUGCCUUAUCCCUGAACUUGGUUUAAUCAAAUCAAUGUGUGUAUUAGAAUAAAAGUCACAGCAUCAAAAAGCCAAAUGAACACAGAUGUGUCUUAAAAUAGUACUAGAGCAGAAACAAGCACUAGUCGUGAUUGUUUUUCAAGAUUUUAUGACUUCUGGGGUAAAAUUCUCUGUUGAGAGACACAAAGGUGCAAAUGAUGGGUGUUGCUUAAAAUGCUAAGAAGGGUCAUGGACGCCCUAAGCUGAGCAUCUUGUUUAGUACCAGGUACUUUCAUCCCUUCUUGACUCCAUCUGCCUUCUGUCCUGGGGGGCCUUGGUUCCAGAAACCAGCUCCCUUCUGAUCAGGUAUUGUCAUUAAUAAACUGUGUGGUACCAGUCCAGUUUAAUAGAGGACUACAGAAGAAAUUAAAACACAAAUAAAUGAGUUAGGACUAUAGAGGUAUUUUAGAUAUGGUGGGAGAUGGUAGAAGAAAUAUGUAUUUAAUGUAGAGCCUGCCAGUGCUUUCAUAUCUUGCUUCCUGCUCUGUCUUCAUAAGAACUGUGUCAUUCUUCUUAUAAAUGAGGGUCUGUGUGACCCUGAGUGUCCAUCUUCAUAGCAGUUAAGUAGAUAGGACAUUACAAUAAUAUAUUUAAAAUUUAAAAUGA